ACUCUGCAAGAAGGCAAUCCUCUAAGGAUCACCAGCUUCUACCUAUAAGACUUCAACUCAAGAUGCAGUAUGGAGGGGCUCCCGGAGGGCCUGCGUUUCCCGGACAAACUCAGGAUCCGCUGUAUGGUUACUUUGCUGCUGUAGCUGGACAGGAUGGGCAGAUAGAUGCUGAUGAAUUGCAGAGAUGUCUGACACAGUCUGGCAUUGCUGGAGGAUACAAACCUUUUAACCUGGAGACUUGCCGGCUUAUGGUUUCAAUGCUGGAUAGAGAUAUGUCUGGCACAAUGGGUUUCAAUGAAUUUAAAGAACUCUGGGCUGUACUGAAUGGCUGGAGACAACACUUUAUCAGUUUUGACACUGACAGGAGUGGAACAGUAGACCCACAAGAAUUGCAGAAGGCCCUGACAACAAUGGGAUUUAGGUUGAGUCCCCAGGCUGUGAAUUCAAUUGCAAAACGAUACAGCACCAAUGGAAAGAUCACCUUCGACGACUACAUCGCCUGCUGCGUCAAACUGAGGGCUCUUACAGACAGCUUUCGAAGACGGGAUACUGCUCAGCAAGGUGUUGUGAAUUUCCCAUAUGAUGAUUUCAUUCAAUGUGUCAUGAGUGUUUAAAUCAAGAGGAAGCUGCAUGAAUGUAAUCAACAUUCCAACUGGAGCUCUCCUUUGCUUGUCCUCUUUGCCUUCGGUAAUAUGUAUAAACUUACAUCACGACUUUCUCUUAACAGCUGUUGUAAAGUUUAUUACUUUAUGUACAACUGAAGUUUUGUUUUAGUUUUGAUAAUAAAUUCUUUGGAACUUUAAUAAGAUCUAGUCUGUUACACCAUUUAGAACUUUCCUGAGCCAUUAUCAGUCAUGCCUUAUUUUCUUGCUAAAACUCUAUGUAAAUUUAAGUAUGCAAAAUGUUUAAGUCACAUUAUUUAUUUUUCAUUGUGAGACACUAAAAACUGUUAAUCAGACUACAGCUGUUAUCUUUCCUCUCCUACAAAGAAUACUCCACACAUAAAAACUUAGGUAAAUGACAUAGACGCACUUGGGUGAAAUAAAACAACAAAAAAGGUAAUCCAGUAAUCCACGUCAGGAUUCACCUUAGAAGUUUAGCACACGCCCUUCAAAACCUGUUGAAUAAUUUGAUUGGCAAAUACUAUCUGUCACCAAGUCCCUUUUUGUCAUCUAUUUAAACCUUUGUUAACUCUCCUUAAAAAUCUUGUACAUUAUAAGCUUAACUAUAUAAAAAGAAAAUUGAUAGAAAAAGACUAAGGGAAUAUAUGGAAAUAUUAACAAUGUUUAUUUUGGAUGAAUGGAAUUCUAGAUGACUUUAAUUUUCUUUAUAUCAGUAUUUUUCAGAUUUUCUAUAUGCUUUCCUUUUAAAAUCAGAUUUUAGUUUUUAAAAUACUGAUACAUCCAUUUUGAUAUACCAUGUAUUCACACUUUAAAAAAUACACAUAGCAGAGUAUCGGAAAGUAUGUACCAAAACAUUGAUCUGGCUACCACUGGGAGUCAGGAUCAUGAGUUCAUCUUCUUCCUUCUUACUGCUUUUCCAAACAUUCUCCAGUAAGCAGGUACUACAUUUAUAAUGGAAGGAAUUUUUUAAAAAAUUUUAAGCUGUACACUUUCAAGUAAGAUCUGAAUUCUAAUGCUGGCUUGUGCCUCUUACUAUGUGGUUUGGUCAUUAUAGAUAAUGCCCAGUUUCAGUUUCCCCAUCUUUGAAAAGGAGAUAAUAUGUUAUCUCUUGGGAGUAGUUCUGAAUAUGAAGUGUGUUGAUACAAGAAGCACUGACAAUGUUUCUGUUUCUUAAAUUUAAAACUGGCCUGGUUUGCCUUUUUUAUCAAGAGAGCUUAACAGAUAAAAAAUGAAAUUAGUCUAUUUUCUACUUGCCAGCAGAGUAUCUGUCUUAUUUUAGGAUGCAGUGUGAAACUUACCAUUCAACUGAACAACUAGUUGUCAACUAAUGAAAAUAAAACAUUUUCUCUAAGCA